ACGGCGGGCCCCGCAGCGCCGGACGCUGGUUGCGCGCUCCCAGGCGCCGAGCGGCCCCGGGCACGCGCGCGCGCCACCGGCCCGGCAGGUGGGUCCCGGCUCCCACGCCGCCUCUCCCGCCCGCGGGACCCUGGGCCGUGGGCUCCGCAGCCCGCCCUGUGCCUCCGGGAGGGGCGUUCCGGGCGCGGGGGGAACGGCCGAGGGCUGGAGACCCUAAAGGCGCCUCCUACGGCCAGAGGGGAGCCUCCGGCGGGAGCCACCUCUCCGGGGCGCAUCAUCCUGCCCCCCAGUAAGAGGAAGGCUCCAGAAUGGAGCUCAGGAAUUAGGAGUCUCGAGUGCUGUCCUUAUUCCCAGCCCAGUCAAGAGCUACCGGGGCUGGCUAGUCAUGGGGGAGCCCAGUAGAGAGGAGUAUAAAAUCCAGUCCUUUGAUGCAGAGACCCAGCAGCUGCUGAAGACAGCACUCAAAGCCCCGUCUCUUGAAUGCACAGUUGCCUGCUUUGAGACAGAAGAUGGAGAAUAUUCCGUUUGCCAGAGGAGCUAUAGUAAUUGCUCUCGCCUGAUGCCUUCCCGCUGUAACACGCAGUACAGAGAUCCGGGUGCUGUGGACUUGGAGAAAGUGGCCAAUGUGAUUGUGGACCAUUCUCUGCAGGACUGUGUGUUCAGCAAGGAAGCAGGACGCAUGUGCUACGCCAUCAUUCAGGCAGAGAGUAAACAAGCAGGCCAGAGUGUCUUCCGACGUGGACUCCUCAACCGGCUGCAGCAGGAGUACCAGGCUCGGGAGCAGCUGCGAGCACGCUCCCUGCAGGGCUGGGUCUGCUAUGUCACCUUUAUCUGCAACAUCUUUGACUACCUGAGGGUGAACAACAUGCCCAUGAUGGCCCUGGUGAACCCUGUCUAUGACUGCCUCUUCCGGCUGGCCCAGCCAGACAGUUUGAGCAAGGAGGAGGAGGUGGGUGGCCCCAGCCCUGGCACAAGCACAGAAGGCUGCAGGAUGGACAGUCCAGCUCAGCCGUGUGUCAGCCCACUGCUCACGGAGGUGGACUGUUUGGUGCUGCAGCUGCACCGGGUUGGGGAGCAGCUGGAGAAAAUGAAUGGGCAGCGCAUGGAUGAGCUCUUUGUGCUGAUCCGGGAUGGCUUCCUGCUCCCAACUGGCCUCAGCUCCCUGGCCCAGCUGCUGCUGCUGGAGAUCAUUGAGUUCCGGGCGGCCGGCUGGAAGACAACGCCAGCUGCCCACAAGUAUUACUACAGCGAAGUCUCCGACUAGGCCUCCAGAUCAGGGCUUCCUCACCAGCACUGGCCUUUCUUCUACCCACCUCUAAAGCUGGCAGUGGAGUCUCUGCCUCACCCAAAGACUUUUCCCUUCCAGACUUUGAGUGUCUUCCCUUCUAGACUUUCCCAUCUCCUGGUGAGAUGUUUCCCACUUAUGCCGUGGUCCUGCCCUGAGCCCCUUUCCCCACCACAACCCACCACGGCCAGGCAGAGAAGGGCAACUCCCAAGAGCCACUGCACUGUGUAACCAUUAGUGCAACUACUACCUUGGUGCCUCAGUUUACCCAUCUGUAAAAUGGGUAAGCAUAGCCACUGGUGGGAUAUUUUGGGAUGUCAAGGGGUGGAGGCAGAGCACAAGUCACACCAGAAACUGCUUUUUAUACAUUUUGUAUAAGGACAACUCUGGAAACAAGCCUAUUUCCUCCAGCCAGUUUCACUGAAUGCUGCACCACAUGCUACACCAGUUCAGCGUGAGAAUUUUCUAAUAAAUCUUUUCUGAUACUAAAA